CUGGUACCUCCUGCCAGCAUCUCUUGGGUUUGCUGAGAACUCACGGGCUCCAGCUACCUGGCCAUGACCACCACAUUUCUGCAAACUUCUUCCUCCACCUUUGGGGGUGGCUCAACCCGAGGGGGUUCCCUCCUGGCUGGGGGAGGUGGCUUUGGUGGGGGGAGUCUCUCUGGGGGAGGUGGAAGCCGAAGUAUCUCAGCUUCUUCUGCUAGGUUUGUCUCUUCAGGGUCAGGAGGAGGAUAUGGGGGUGGCAUGAGGGUCUGUGGCUUUGGUGGAGGGGCUGGUAGUGUUUUCGGUGGAGGCUUUGGAGGGGGCGUUGGUGGGGGUUUUGGUGGUGGCUUUGGUGGUGGCGAUGGUGGUCUCCUCUCUGGCAAUGAGAAAAUUACCAUGCAGAACCUCAAUGACCGCCUGGCCUCCUACCUGGACAAGGUACGUGCCCUGGAGGAGGCCAAUGCUGACCUGGAGGUGAAGAUCCAUGACUGGUACCAGAAGCAGACCCCAACCAGCCCAGAAUGCGACUACAGCCAAUACUUCAAGACCAUUGAAGAGCUCCGGGACAAGAUCAUGGCCACCACCAUCGACAACUCCCGGGUCAUCCUGGAGAUCGACAAUGCCAGGCUGGCUGCGGACGACUUCAGGCUCAAGUAUGAGAAUGAGCUGGCCCUGCGCCAGGGCGUUGAGGCUGACAUCAACGGCUUGCGCCGAGUCCUGGAUGAGCUGACCCUGGCCAGGACUGACCUGGAGAUGCAGAUCGAGGGCCUGAAUGAGGAGCUAGCCUACCUGAAGAAGAACCACGAAGAGUGGGUCCCUCCCAUCCUGCAGGAGAUGAAGGAGUUCAGCAGCCAGCUGGCCGGCCAGGUCAAUGUGGAGAUGGACGCAGCACCGGGUGUGGACCUGACCCGUGUGCUGGCAGAGAUGAGGGAGCAGUACGAGGCCAUGGCGGAGAAGAACCGCCGGGAUGUCGAGGCCUGGUUCUUCAGCAAGACUGAGGAGCUGAACAAAGAGGUGGCCUCCAACACAGAAAUGAUCCAGACCAGCAAGACGGAGAUCACAGACCUGAGACGCACGAUGCAGGAGCUGGAGAUCGAGCUGCAGUCCCAGCUCAGCAUGAAAGCUGGGCUGGAGAACUCACUGGCCGAGACAGAGUGCCGCUAUGCCACGCAGCUGCAGCAGAUCCAGGGGCUCAUUGGUGGCCUGGAGGCCCAGCUGAGUGAGCUCCGAUGCGAGAUGGAGGCUCAGAACCAGGAGUACAAGAUGCUGCUUGACAUAAAGACACGGCUGGAGCAGGAGAUCGCUACUUACCGCAGCCUGCUCGAGGGCCAGGAUGCCAAGAUGGCUGGCAUUGCCAUCAGGGAAGCCUCUUCAGGAGGUGGUGGUAGCAGCAGCAAUUUCCACAUCAAUGUAGAAGAGUCAGUGGAUGGACAGGUGGUUUCUUCCCACAAGAGAGAAAUCUAAGUGUCUAUUGCAGGAGAAACGUCCCUUGCCACUCCCCACUCUCAUCAGGCCAAGUGGAGGACUGGCCAGAGGGCCUGCACAUGCAAACUCCAGUCCCUGCCUUCAGAGAGCUGAAAAGGGUCCCUCGGUCUUUUAUUUCAGGGCUUUGCAUGCGCUCUAUUCCCCCUCUGCCUCUCCCCACCUUCUUUGGAGCAAGGAGAUGCAGCUGUAUUGUGUAACAAGCUCAUUUGUACAGUGUCUGUUCAUGUAAUAAAGAAUUACUUUUCCUUUUGCAAAUA